GGGAAGGGAAUGUGACCAGGUCUAGGUCUGGAGUUUCAGCUUGGACACUGAGCCAAGCAGACAAGCAAAGCAAGCCAGGACACACCAUCCUGCCCCAGGCCCAGCUUCUCUCCUGCCUUCCAACGCCAUGGGGAGCAAUCUCAGCCCCCAACUCUGCCUGAUGCCCUUUAUCUUGGGCCUCUUGUCUGGAGGUGUGACCACCACUCCAUGGUCUUUGGCCCAGCCCCAGGGAUCCUGCUCUCUGGAGGGGGUAGAGAUCAAAGGCGGCUCCUUCCGACUUCUCCAAGAGGGCCAGGCACUGGAGUACGUGUGUCCUUCUGGCUUCUACCCGUACCCUGUGCAGACACGUACCUGCAGAUCUACGGGGUCCUGGAGCACCCUGAAGACUCAAGACCAAAAGACUGUCAGGAAGGCAGAGUGCAGAGCAAUCCACUGUCCAAGACCACACGACUUCGAGAACGGGGAAUACUGGCCCCGGUCUCCCUACUACAAUGUGAGUGAUGAGAUCUCUUUCCACUGCUAUGACGGUUACACUCUCCGGGGCUCUGCCAAUCGCACCUGCCAAGUGAAUGGCCGGUGGAGUGGGCAGACAGCGAUCUGUGACAACGGAGCGGGGUACUGCUCCAACCCGGGCAUCCCCAUUGGCACAAGGAAGGUGGGCAGCCAGUACCGCCUUGAAGACAGCGUCACCUACCACUGCAGCCGGGGGCUUACCCUGCGUGGCUCCCAGCGGCGAACGUGUCAGGAAGGUGGCUCUUGGAGCGGGACGGAGCCUUCCUGCCAAGACUCCUUCAUGUACGACACCCCUCAAGAGGUGGCCGAAGCUUUCCUGUCUUCCCUGACAGAGACCAUAGAAGGAGUCGAUGCUGAGGAUGGGCACGGCCCAGGGGAACAACAGAAGCGGAAGAUCGUCCUGGACCCUUCAGGCUCCAUGAACAUCUACCUGGUGCUAGAUGGAUCAGACAGCAUUGGGGCCAGCAACUUCACAGGAGCCAAAAAGUGUCUAGUCAACUUAAUUGAGAAGGUGGCAAGUUAUGGUGUGAAGCCAAGAUAUGGUCUAGUGACAUAUGCCACAUACCCCAAAAUUUGGGUCAAAGUGUCUGAAGCAGACAGCAGUAAUGCAGACUGGGUCACGAAGCAGCUCAAUGAAAUCAAUUAUGAAGACCACAAGUUGAAGUCAGGGACUAACACCAAGAAGGCCCUCCAGGCAGUGUACAGCAUGAUGAGCUGGCCAGAUGACGUCCCUCCUGAAGGCUGGAACCGCACCCGCCAUGUCAUCAUCCUCAUGACUGAUGGAUUGCACAACAUGGGCGGGGACCCAAUUACUGUCAUUGAUGAGAUCCGGGACUUGCUAUACAUUGGCAAGGAUCGCAAAAACCCAAGGGAGGAUUAUCUGGAUGUCUAUGUGUUUGGGGUCGGGCCUUUGGUGAACCAAGUGAACAUCAAUGCUUUGGCUUCCAAGAAAGACAAUGAGCAACAUGUGUUCAAAGUCAAGGAUAUGGAAAACCUGGAAGAUGUUUUCUACCAAAUGAUCGAUGAAAGCCAGUCUCUGAGUCUCUGUGGCAUGGUUUGGGAACACAGGAAGGGUACCGAUUACCACAAGCAACCAUGGCAGGCCAAGAUCUCAGUCAUUCGCCCUUCAAAGGGACACGAGAGCUGUAUGGGGGCUGUGGUGUCUGAGUACUUUGUGCUGACAGCAGCACAUUGUUUCACUGUGGAUGACAAGGAACACUCAAUCAAGGUCAGCGUAGGAGGGGAGAAGCGGGACCUGGAGAUAGAAGUAGUCCUAUUUCACCCCAACUACAACAUUAAUGGGAAAAAAGAAGCAGGAAUUCCUGAAUUUUAUGACUAUGACGUUGCCCUGAUCAAGCUCAAGAAUAAGCUGAAAUAUGGCC